GUACUCUGUGAGCGGCGCCCGGGCGCCUGGGCAGGCGCCUCCCGAGUACCGGCGCCCAUUUUGCCCGCCCGCUAAGGAGACCCGUGCGCGGCCUACACGCUUGGGGGACAGCCCUUUAAGACGACAUCUCCGCGAACGCCGGCCUCUUGAGCCAGGGGGACGCUCUUUUGAAAGUCAGUCCCAAAACAGUUAAGGUUUUAUUUUAUUUUGUUUUAUUUCCAAGUCACAGCCCCCGAAUCUCGUACAACUCUCCCUGGACCACUUCCGGUUGCCGGCCCGCGCCUCAUAACUUCGGUUCGAGUGACCUCGGCCCGGGAUGCCCCUCGGCUCACCCCGGGCUCACGUCGCGAUCCUGGCUUGAGUGGCCCAGGGUGGGAGACCUGGAAGUUUUAGCCUAGCUGUUCUCAAGGCGGAUUAAUUAGCCCAAGAAACAUUAUAUUCAUUUUUCUGGAUAUGCCGCAGAAGGAUCCGUGCCAGAAGCAAGCCUGUGAGAUACAGAAAUGUUUACAAGCCAACAGCUACAUGGAAUCAAAGUGUCAGGCUGUCAUCCAAGAACUGCGUAAGUGUUGUGCUCAGUAUCCCAAGGGAAGAUCUGUCGUCUGUUCAGGAUUUGAAAAAGAAGAGGAAGAAAACCUAACACGGAAGUCUGCAUCAAAGUAAAGUUCUUCUGAAGUGCUGCUCCAUGUUUCCACCAAAUGAAUUUUUUUUAUCCUCCUGACUCUUCAGGCCAGGUAGCAGCAAAUAGCAAAUGAAAAAGUCAGCUACAAAAGUUAAUGAAUAUGCCAUCUAUGCAGAACAGGCAGAAAUAUAAACACAUUAAAAGACAAAUAUGUAGAAUGUAAUAUACUGAGCUGCUAAAAUAAACCUGUUUAAGAGAAAAA